AUGCGUAGUCUCGGCCCCGGGCUGCCGCGCCAGCCCGUCUCCGCGGCGGGGGACCGGGCUGCCUUGGCCCCUCAGCGCUCGCGUCUUUUCCGGCAGUUGGAACGCUUCCUGUUGUCCUCACCCGUAACCGCCUGUUGCCCCCUGUCUCAGAGUCCCUCACGCGUCCCCUCCCGUCUUUGGCUCGUUGGCUGCCGCCGCCGGGGCUUCGCCAGCCUUCAAGUCGAGACUACUGGCCGAAGGGGCGUCUGCGGCUCUCCGCCGUCCCCAGCCCUGCCUCUCCCUGGGCUCUGACGGAGUCUCACUCACCCAGGCUAGAGUGCAGUGGUGUGAUCUUGGCUCACUGCAACCUGUGCCUCCAGGGUUCAAGCGAUUCUCCUGCCUCAGCCUCCCAAGUAGCUGGGAUUACAGGUGCCCACCACCACACCCGGCUAAUUUUUUUUGUAUUUUUAGUAGAGACAGGCUUUCACCAUGUUGGCCAAGCUAGUCUCCAACUCCUGACUUCAGGUGAUCCACCUGCCUCAGCCUCCCAAAGUUCUGGGAUUACAGGCAUGAGCCACCGUGUCCGGCCAUCUUUAUUCUUUAGCUUUGUUGACAACUAAAAAUCAUUAACUUACUCAACUGCCUGUUAUAUGGAAGGCACUGUUUGCCUUAGGGUUAAAUACUAGCAGAUUGUUGUGUUGUGUUUGUUGUUGUUGUUGUUGUUUUUAAGACAGAGUCUUGCUCUGUCCCAGGCUGGCGUGCAGUGGCACAAGCCAAACUCACUGAAACCUCUGCCUCUCCAGCUCAAGCAAUCCUCCCACCUCAGCCUCCUGAGUAGCUGGGACUACAGGUGUGUGCUACCACACCUGGCCAAUUUUUUGUAUUUUUUUGUAGCAACGGGGGUUUUGCCAUGUUGCACAGGCUGGUUUCAAGCAAUCUCCUACCUCUCCCUCCCAAAGUGCUGAGAUUACAGGGGUGCACCAGUGCCCUGGCAAAUUGUUACAUUUUUAUGUUGAAGUAAUUUCAGUUGUUAAAAUGUAACUACAUAUAUGCAAUUUCUUCAGGAAUUUUCAGACAAGGAAGUACAAAACUCUCACUUGCUUUUGACAUGUUUUUACAUCUGGUUUUUAAAUUUCUUCACCAAACACACUUAGAGUGCAUGUGGUUUUCAUUGUGGGUGGAGGGGGGGGUACAGGCUGACAAAUAAGGAACCACACCCAAGCUUCACAAACCAAACAGAGGUUUUUUUUUUGUUGUUUUUGUUUUUUUUAAUUCCUUUAGUGAUACUCUAAAACAUUUGAGUUUGCUUUGGUAUUAGUCGAAACUUCCCCAUAAAAAAUAAUGUGAUAUUUUAUAGUAAGGUAGCUCUUAAUGCAGUGUCUUAAAUUUGUUUUUACUGAUCUUUUUGGCACAUGAUGAAUCAAAAUGUUUGACUCUCAAGUAGAGUCUUAGUUUUGAAUCUCUGCUCUGAAGGAAUUAUUUAUGUGAUUUUUGUCUGCGUAUCUUUUUAAAUAAUUGCUUUUUAAAUAAUUUUAAGGCUUUUUUGAACAAGUGUUUUAUAAGCCUUAGUUUAAUCCACAAAACAAUUUAAAAAGCUACUAAAUAUUAAGGGGGAAAACCUGAAAACUUUUCUUAAAAUGCACUAUCUUUGAAAAUGGUCCUUGGCUGGGUGCGGUGGCUUAUGCCUCUAAUCCCAGCACUUUGGGAGGCCCAGGCAGUCAGAUCAUCUGAGGUCAGGAGUUCAAGACUAGCCUGGCCAACAUAGUGAAACCCCGUCUCUACUAAAAACUAGCUGGGGGUGAUGGCAUGUCCCUGUAGUCCCAACUACUUGGGAGGCUGAGGCAGGAGAAUCGCUUGAACCCAGGAGGCGGAGGUUGCAGUGCACCGAGAUUGUGCCAUUGCACUCCAGCCUGGGCGACAGAGUGAGACUCCAUUUCCAAAAAAAGAAAAAUGGCCCUUUGACUCUCAUGAUUCUUUUUUGCUGCAGCUGUGGGGGGUAGUAGAGACAGGGUCUUGCUAUGUUACCCAGGCUGGUCUUGAAUUCCUGGACUCAUGAACUCCUGGGCUCAAAUGAUCUCUCUACCUCACCCUCCCAAAGUGAUGGGAUUACAGGCAUGAACCACAGUGUUCAGCCUCUCCUAAUUUUUACUCAGCUUUAUAUUGGGAUGAAGAGACAGAGAAGUAGAUCAUAUGAGAGGUAGGAAUGGUAAGAAUAAAAUAUUGAGCACUAUUGGCCGGGCAUGGUGGCUCACGCCUGUAAUCCCAGCACUUUGGGAGGCUGAGAUGGGCAGAUCAUGAGGUCAGGAGAUCGAGACCAUCCUGGCUAACACGGUGAAACCCUGUCUCUACUAAAAAAUAGAAAAAAUUAGCCGGGCGUGGUGGCGGGUGCCUGUAGUCCCAGCUACUCGGGAGGCUGAGGCAGGAGAAUGGCACGAACCUGGGAGGCGGAGCUUGGAGUGAGCCGAGAUCGCGCCACUGCACUCCAGCCUGGGCGACAGAGCGAGACUUCGUCUCAAAAAAAAAAAAAUUGAGCGCUAUUGCCAAUGCUGGAGCAAGUCAAUGUUAGUGAACAAUUUGGCCAAGUGUGAUAAUACAGGUUAGCUGAAAUAUCUGGAGGAAAACAAGAUUUUAUUUUAUUUAUUUAUUUUUUUUGAGACGGAAUCUUGCUCUGUCACCCAGGUGGAGUGCAGUGGCAUGAUCUCGGCUCACUGCAACCUCUGCCUCCCGGGUUCAAGCGAUUCUCCUGUCUCAGCCUCCCGAGUAGCUGGGAUUAUAGGCGCCUGCCACCACGCACAGCUAAUUUUUGUGUUUUUAGUAGAGACGGGGUUUCACUCUGUUGGUCAGGCUAGUCUCCCAACUCCUGACCUCAGAUGAUUCGCCUGCCUUGGCCUCCCAAAGUGCUGGGAUUACAGGCGUGAGCCACCGCGCUCAGCCGAUUUUAUUAUUUAUUUUUGAGACUGAGUCUCGCUGUGUAGCCCAGUCUGGAGUGCAGUGGCGCUAUCUCGGCUCACUGCAACCUCUGCUUCCCAAUUCAAGCAAUUCUGCCUCAGCCUUUGGAGUAGCUAGGACUACUGGUGUGUGCCACACUCCUGGUUGAAAACAAUAUUUUAAAUUUAGGAAAAAAAUAUUCUAUAACUUAUCUAAACACAUUGGUGGUGUUUUUUUCUUGUGUAAAAUGAGGAAAUUAAGAUCUCUUGUUUUUAAGGUAUUGCUGCUUCUACCACUAGAAUCGUGAUUCAGGUUUUUUGUCAUAUUGUUCCCUUUAUUUUAAGACUUAAAACUUUAUUUUAACUUGUAAAUUCAAAUAAACGGCAAACAUUUAUCAAAUACCUUAAGGCUGUGUCAGAGCAUAUAUGUAUCAGAUUACCAUUUUUAAUCAUAGAUUUUUCUUUUAACUGUGGAUAAACUUAAAAAGUUAUUGGUAACAGUAUAUGCUUAUGGAAGAAAAUAUAGAAAAACAUGGGCUGGGUGCAGUGGCUCAUGCCUGCAAUCCCAGCACUUUGGGAGGCCAAGUUGGGUGGAUCACUUGAGGUCAAGAGUUUGAGACCAGCCUGACCAGUGUGGUGAAACCCCGUCUCUACUGAAAAUACAAAAAAAAAAAUUAGCUGGGCACAGUGGCUGGUGCCUGUCAUCUUAACUACUUGGGAGGCUGAGACACGAGAAUCGCUUGAACCUGGGAGGCAGAGGUUCCAGUGAGCUGAGAUUGAAUCAUUGUACUCCAGCAUGGGCGACAGAGUGAGACUCCAUCUCAAAAAAAAAAAAAAAGAAAAAGAAAAACAUGGAAAAAGCACAAGCAAGAAUAACAUUUUCUAUUCCCACUACCUACAGCCAGGUGUGGUGGCGCAUGCCUGUAAUCCCAGCUACUCGGGAAACUGAGGUGGGAGAAUCGAUUGAACCUGGAAGGUGGAGGUUGCGGUGAGCCAAGAUCAUCCUGUCGCACUCCAGCCUGGGCAACAAGAGCGAAACUCCAUCUCAAAAAGAAAAAAAAAGAUAUAUUUGUGUGACUUACAGGUACAGCCAUGGCAAUGACAGGCUCAACACCUUGCUCAUCCAUGAGUAACCACACAAAGGAAAGGGUGACAAUGACCAAAGUGACACUGGAGAAUUUUUAUAGCAACCUUAUCGCUCAACAUGAAGAACGAGAAAUGAGACAAAAGAAGUUAGAAAAGGUGAUGGAAGAAGAAGGCCUAAAAGAUGAGGAGAAACGACUCCGGAGAUCAGCACAUGCUCGGAAGGAAACAGAGUUUCUUCGUUUGAAGAGAACAAGACUUGGAUUGGAAGAUUUUGAGUCCUUAAAAGUAAUAGGCAGAGGAGCAUUUGGUGAGGUACGGCUUGUUCAGAAGAAAGAUACGGGACAUGUGUAUGCAAUGAAAAUACUCCGUAAAGCAGAUAUGCUUGAAAAAGAGCAGGUUGGCCACAUUCGUGCGGAGCGUGACAUUCUAGUGGAGGCAGACAGUUUGUGGGUUGUGAAAAUGUUCUAUAGUUUUCAGGAUAAGCUAAACCUCUACCUAAUCAUGGAGUUCCUGCCUGGAGGGGACAUGAUGACCUUGUUGAUGAAAAAAGACACUCUGACAGAAGAGGAGACUCAGUUUUAUAUAGCAGAAACAGUAUUAGCCAUAGACUCUAUUCACCAACUUGGAUUCAUCCACAGAGACAUCAAACCAGACAACCUUCUUUUGGACAGCAAGGGCCAUGUGAAACUUUCUGACUUUGGUCUUUGCACAGGACUGAAAAAAGCACAUAGGACAGAAUUUUAUAGGAAUCUGAACCACAGCCUCCCCAGUGAUUUCACUUUCCAGAACAUGAAUUCCAAAAGGAAAGCAGAAACCUGGAAAAGAAAUAGACGUCAGCUAGCCUUCUCCACAGUAGGCACUCCUGACUACAUUGCUCCUGAGGUGUUCAUGCAGACCGGGUACAACAAGCUCUGUGAUUGGUGGUCGCUUGGGGUGAUCAUGUAUGAGAUGCUCAUCGGCUACCCACCUUUCUGUUCUGAGACCCCUCAAGAGACAUAUAAGAAGGUGAUGAACUGGAAAGAAACUUUGACUUUUCCUCCAGAAGUUCCCAUCUCUGAGAAAGCCAAGGAUCUAAUUUUGAGGUUCUGCUGUGAAUGGGAACAUAGAAUUGGAGCUCCUGGAGUUGAGGAAAUAAAAAGUAACUCUUUUUUUGAAGGCGUUGACUGGGAACAUAUCAGAGAGAGACCUGCUGCAAUAUCUAUUGAAAUCAAAAGCAUUGAUGAUACCUCAAACUUCGAUGAGUUUCCAGAAUCUGAUAUUCUUAAGCCAACAGUGGCCACAAGUAAUCAUCCUGAGACUGACUACAAGAACAAAGACUGGGUCUUCAUCAAUUACACGUACAAGCGCUUUGAGGGCCUGACUGCAAGGGGGGCAAUACCUUCCUACAUGAAAGCAGCAAAAUAGUACUCUUGCCACGGAAUCCUAUGUGGAGCAGAGUUCUUUGUAUAACAUCAUGCUUUUCCUCUCACACUCUUGAAGAGCUUCCAAGAAGUUGAUGGAACCCACCAAUAUGUCAUAGUAAAGUCUCCUGAAAUGUGGUAGUAAGAGGAUUUUCUUCCAUAAUGCAUCUGAAAAACUGUAAACAAAGACAACCAUUUCUACUACGUCGGCCAUAAACAGCUAUCCUGCUUUGGAAGAGAAGCAUCAUGAGCCAAUUUGAUAGGUGUUUUAAAAAUAACUUGAGUUUUCCUAAGUUCAUCAGAAUGAAGGGGAAAAACAGCCAUCAUCCAACAUUAUUGAGAUUGUCGUGUAUAGUCAUCGAAUAUCAGCCAGUUCCUGUAAUUUUGUGACACGCUCUCUGCCAAGCCCACCAAGUAUUUCCUUUAUAGCUAAAAGUUCCAUAGUACUAAGGAAAUAAAGCAAUAAAGACAGUCUCAGCAGCCAGGAUUCUGGCUGAAGGAAAUGAUCCGCCACCCUGAGGGUGGUGAUGGUAGUUUCUACCCAUACCUCAGCCUCAGGCGAGUGGCUUAUAGCCUCCAUUCAUGGUGCACUUUAUUUAUGGUACUAAGAUAAAGACUGUCAAUCCAUUGAUUUAUCUCCUCCUGUCCCCCAUCUAAAAUACCCAUGCUGCUUUUCUGAGUGUUGAUGGGGGUUACCAGCUUGAUCCACUGUUGCUCUUAGAAGGCCCAGAAAGUCUUUGGGCAUUGCCAAGAAAUCCCGGAUUAUGUGGAAAACCCUCACUUUCUCUUCACGGCUGUACCAGAAAAUCCCUAAGACAGAUCUUGCCGUGGACUAGCAAUACCUGCAAGUGCUGCCAAUGGGAACUCAAUUUAUUCCUGGGAACCUAACGAGGAGAGCCCAGGCCUAGGCAGGAGGCCUGGAACCCUCUUGGCUAAGGUGCUGUUCCUGUUCCUGCAAGGUCUCCAGAACCCCUUUGGAAAUGGUGAAGGAACCAGCCCAAUAGAAGUACAGAGCCAGCUGACAAGUCCUUGUAAAGCUCACUCCUCAGUCCUUGGCACAGCCAUGUUUUGUCUUCUCUCUUGGUAUUUCUUCUCUCCCAACUUUAGCCAUUUUGCCUUGGAAUCAUGAUUACAAUUUUUUCCUUUGCAGAUGCCUUCCUGGGGGAUACUCCUCCCCACCCUAAAGGGUCGCCUGCAACUUAGGCGGAUUGGGUCUCUCUGCUGUGGCGUUCUCUCUUGAGAGACCCUCUGAAUUUUAGCACAAAGUGCCUUCUGUUUCACAGCUGCCACCACCUUUAGAGGAAUUUCGUCAGAAAAAUGUGGAGGCUCCAUAUUAAUGCAUUAUUUUUUAAAAAGUUUUGAUAACUCUUAAAGCAUCAUUUGCACCUAUGUGGGAACUUUGCCUGUUGCAAAGUAUUGUGGCCGAGCUGCAGCUGGGAGCCUGCUUUCUGCCAGUCUUGAGGUUCUGAAGAUCAGCUUUGAAAGGAAAGUAUGUCCUAGCUUAGCCAUUCAGAAGAGAAAAAUGGAAUAUCAGAGUUACAGUUGUCAGUGAAACUACUUUGGAUUUUAACCUCUUAGAGGAAGAAAAAAGGUUAGGGAAGUGUCAACUCUGGAUGAAGGUGAUGUGUUUGCCUCUCAGUCUUUCAUUCAUAGCCUGCUAGUGAAAAGGAAGUAAAUGAGAUUCUUUUGUGUGACUUUGUAGUCUCUUUGUAUUACCAAAUAGUUGGGGUGUUGACUCCUGUGUGUUUUGCAAGAAUGUGUGGUAAGCCUGGGUAAAGAGAAGGAACUGCGGUGUUGGGAGAGUCUUUGUGUUGGGGAGUGGCAGGGGAUGAUUUGUUUCAGGGGAAAAUGCCCACAUUUUAACUUUUAAACUUCUGAAUAAACUGUGUAAAAACA